AAUUUCGGUUCUCACAGACUCUUACUUGGAUGUCUGUAAAUCCGGCUGGACUUUCAGCUUCUAAGAACAGUCCGUUUCUCGAGGAUCCAGGCGCAGGAGGACAGAGCAAUGGGUGAGAGAACUCUUCACGCUGCAGUGCCCACACCAGGUUAUCCAGAAUCUGAAUCCAUCAUGAUGGCCCCCAUUUGUCUAGUGGAAAACCAGGAAGAGCAGCUGACAGUGAAUUCAAAGGCAUUAGAGAUUCUUGACAAGAUUUCUCAGCCCGUGGUGGUGGUGGCCAUUGUAGGGCUAUACCGCACAGGAAAAUCCUAUCUCAUGAAUCGUCUUGCAGGAAAGCGCAAUGGCUUCCCUCUGGGCUCCACGGUGCAGUCUGAAACUAAGGGCAUCUGGAUGUGGUGUGUGCCCCACCUCUCUAAGCCAAACCACACCCUGGUCCUUCUGGACACCGAGGGCCUGGGCGAUGUAGAAAAGAGUAACCCUAAGAAUGACUCGUGGAUCUUUGCCCUGGCUGUGCUUCUAAGCAGCAGCUUUGUCUAUAACAGCGUGAGCACCAUCAACCACCAGGCCCUGGAGCAGCUGCACUAUGUGACUGAGCUAGCAGAGCUAAUCAGGGCAAAAUCCUGCCCCAGACCUGAUGAAGCUGAGGACUCCAGCGAGUUUGCGAGUUUCUUUCCAGACUUUAUUUGGACUGUUCGGGAUUUUACCCUGGAGCUAAAGUUAGAUGGAAACCCCAUCACAGAAGAUGAGUACCUGGAGAAUGCCUUGAAGCUGAUUCCAGGCAAGAAUCCCAAAAUUCAAAAUUCAAACAUGCCUAGAGAGUGUAUCAGGCAUUUCUUCCGAAAACGGAAGUGCUUUGUCUUUGACCGGCCUACAAAUGACAAGCAAUAUUUAAAUCAUAUGGACGAAGUGCCAGAAGAAAAUCUGGAAAGGCAUUUCCUUAUGCAAUCAGACAACUUCUGUUCUUAUAUCUUCACCCAUGCAAAGACCAAGACCCUGAGAGAGGGAAUCAUUGUCACUGGAAAGCGGCUGGGGACUCUGGUGGUGACUUAUGUAGAUGCCAUCAACAGUGGAGCAGUACCUUGUCUGGAGAAUGCAGUGACAGCACUGGCCCAGCUUGAGAACCCAGCGGCUGUGCAGAGGGCAGCCGACCACUAUAGCCAGCAGAUGGCCCAGCAACUGAGGCUCCCCACAGACACGCUCCAGGAGCUGCUGGACGUGCAUGCAGCCUGUGAGAGGGAAGCCAUUGCAGUCUUCAUGGAGCACUCCUUCAAGGAUGAAAACCAUGAAUUCCAGAAGAAGCUUGUGGACACCAUAGAGAAAAAGAAGGGAGACUUUGUGCUGCAGAAUGAAGAGGCAUCUGCCAAAUAUUGCCAGGCUGAGCUUAAGCGGCUUUCAGAGCACCUGACAGAAAGCAUUUUGAGAGGAAUUUUCUCUGUUCCUGGAGGACACAAUCUCUACUUAGAAGAAAAGAAACAGGUUGAGUGGGACUAUAAGCUAGUGCCCAGAAAAGGAGUUAAGGCAAACGAGGUCCUCCAGAACUUCCUGCAGUCACAGGUGGUUGUAGAGGAAUCCAUCCUGCAGUCAGACAAAGCCCUCACUGCUGGAGAGAAGGCCAUAGCAGCGGAGCGGGCCAUGAAGGAAGCAGCUGAGAAGGAACAGGAGCUGCUAAGAGAAAAACAGAAGGAGCAGCAGCAAAUGAUGGAGGCUCAAGAGAGAAGCUUCCAGGAAUACAUGGCCCAAAUGGAGAAGAAGUUGGAGGAGGAAAGGGAAAACCUUCUCAGAGAGCAUGAAAGGCUGCUAAAACACAAGCUGAAGGUACAAGAAGAAAUGCUUAAGGAAGAAUUUCAAAAGAAAUCUGAGCAGUUAAAUAAAGAGAUUAAUCAACUGAAAGAAAAAAUUGAAAGCACUAAAAAUGAACAGUUAAGGCUCUUAAAGAUCCUUGACAUGGCUAGCAACAUAAUGAUUGUCACUCUACCUGGGGCUUCCAAGCUACUUGGAGUAGGGACAAAAUAUCUUGGCUCACGUAUUUAAGAGCCUGAAUAUUCCAGGUAAGAAAAUAUAAAAUGAGGUUUAUUUUAUUUUAAUAACAUAACACUGUUGCUCAUUUUGUAAGUAUAUGUGUUAUAGCAGUUUCAUUCAAGAAAAGUUUAAAAUUAAAAAGUGAUUAUCAAAGAAUAUCAGGGCCUGACAUCCACAAAAAACAAACUUAAUUUUGAUUGAACUAAUAAUUUAUAAACAUGGGAAACAAGUCAGAAGUAGUGACAUUAUUCCUAGAAAAGAUUUAAGGAAAGCAAAAAGACAACUGGUAAGAUUAAGAAGCCAUUAACCAUUUGCAAUUUAUAUUAUAGUCACAGAAAUAAUUUCAGUUAUGACUAGCUCUUGCCGAUUAAUGAGAAGAGAGCAGCUCCACAAUUUUUAAUUUUUUUAACUUUUAUUUUAGAUUCAGGGGUAUAUGUGCAGGUUUGUUACAUAGGUAAACUGCAUGUCAUGGGGGUUUGGUGUGCAGAUAAUUUUAUCACACAAUUAUUAAUCAUAAUACCCAAUAGGUUUUUUUCUGAUCUUCUCCCUCCUCCCAACCUACACCCUCAAGUAGACCCCAGUGUCUCUUGUUCUCCUCUGAGUAUCCAUGUGUUCUCUUUGUUUGGCCCCCAUUUAUAAGUGAGAACAUGUGGUAUUUGGGUUUCUGUUCCUGUGUUAGUUUGCUUAUGAUAAUGGCUUCCAGCUCCAUCCAUAUUGCUACAGAGGACAUGAUCUUGUUGUUUUUUAUGGCUGCAUAGUAUUCCAUGGUGUUUGUAUAUACCACAUUUUCAUUAUCCAGCCUAUUAUUAAUGCACAUUUAGGUUGAUUCCUUAUCUUUGCUAUUGUGAACAGUGCUGCAAUGGACAUACACGUGCAUGUGCCUUUAUGGUACAAUGAUUUAUAUUUCCUUGGGAUAUGCAUUCCUUUGGGAAUAAUGGGAUUGCUGAGUUGAAUGGUAAUUCUGAGUUCUUUGAGGAAUCACCAACCUGCUUUCCACAGUGGCUAAACUAAUUUACACUCCCACCAACAGUGUAUGUGUUCCAUUUUCUCCACAACCUUGCCAGCAUCUGUUAUUUAUUGACUUUCUAGUAACAGCCAUUCUGACUGGUGUGAGAUGGUAUGCAUUUCUGUAGUGAUUAGUGAUGAUGAGUGAUUUUUAUAUGCUUUUUAAAUGCAUAUAUGUCUUCUUUUGAAAUGUGUUCAUGUUCUUUGCCCACUUUCUUUUUAAUGGGGUUGCUUGUUUUUCGCUUGUAAAUUUUUUGAAGCUUCUUAUAGAUUCUGGAUAUUAGAUCUUUGUUGGAUGCAUAGUUGGCAAAUAUUUUCUACCAUUCUGUAGGUUGUCUGUUACUUUGUUAAUUGUUUCAUUUUGUUUUGUUUUUGUUUUUUGAAACAGGGUCUCACUUUGACACCCAGGCUGGAGUGCAGUAGCACAAACAUGGGUCAUUGUAGCCUCAACCUCCCAGGCUCAAGCAGUCCUUUCACCUCAACCCCCCACAUAGCUGGGACUACAGGUGCUUACACCCAAGACCAGUUAAUUUUUUGUAUUUGUUUGUAGAGAUGUGUUUUUCCAUGUUGCCCAAGCUGGUCUUGAACUACUGAGCUCAAGCAAUCUGCCUGCUUCAGCCUCCCAAAGUACUGGGAUUUAGGCAUGAGCCACCACAUCUGGCCAAUAGUUUCUUUUGAUGUGCAGAAGCUCUUUAAUUUAAUUAGAUCUCCUUUGUCAGUUUUUGUUUUUGCUGCAAUUGCUUAUGUUAUCUUCAUCAUGAAAUUUUAGCCAAGUCUUAUGUCCAGAAUGGUAUUUCUUAGGUUAUUUUUCAGAGUUUUUAUAGUUUAAUGUUUUAUAUUUAAGUCUUUAAUCCUUCUUAAGUUGAUUUUUGUAUGCAGAGUAAGCUGGGGGCCCAGUUUCAAUCUUCUGCAUAUGGCUAGCCAGUAAUCCCAGCACCAUUUAUUAAAUGGGGACUUCUUUCCCCAUUGCUUGUUUUUGUCAGCUUUGUCCAAGAUCAGAUGAUUGUAGGUGUACAGCAUUAUUUCUGGACUCUCUGUUAUGUUCCAUUUAUCUGUGUGUCUGUUUUUCUACUAAUACCAUGCUGUUUUGGUUACUGUAGCUCUGUAGUAUGGUUUGAGGUUUGGUAACUUGAUGCCUCCCCUUUUGUUCUUUAUGUUUAGGAUUGCCUUGGCUAGGCUCUUUUUUGGUUCCAUAUGAAUUUUAAAGUAGUUUCUAAUUCUGUGAAGAAUGUCAUUGGUAGUUUGAUAGGGAUAGCAUUGAACUAUUUGCUCAACUCAACAUUUUAGGAAUUUAUUUCUGCUGUCUAGUGCUCAAAACUUGCAGCUAGAAUUGAGGGAAGAGAGAGACCUUCUUAUAUUGUUUUAUAUUGUUUGAUACUCAGUACCUGUUUUAAGAAAAAACAACAAGGAAGUAAAACCAAAGACAGGCAGCCCAGCGCCAGGCCCAAAACCAGGCCUGGGCCUGCCUGGCCUAAACCCAGUAGUUAAAAAUCAACUCAUUGCCUGUAAUCCCAGCACUUUGGGAGGCCGAGACGGGUGGAUCACGAGGUCAGGAGAUCGAGACCAUCCUGGCUAACACGGUGAAACCCCGUCUCUACUAAAAAUACAAAAAUUAGCCGGGCAUGGUGGCACGCGCCUGUAGUCCCAGCUACACGGGAGGCUGAGGCAGGAGAAUGGCGUGAACCCAGGAGGCGGAGCUUGCAGUGAGUCGAGAUCGCGCCACUGCACUCCAGCCUGGGCGACAGAGCGAAACUCCGUCUCAAAAAAAAAAAAAAAAAAUCAACUCAUAACUUAGAAACCGAUGUUAUUCAUAGAUUCCAGACAUUGUAUAGAAGAACAUUUGGAAACUCACUGCCUUGUUCUGUUUCUCUCUGACCACCAGUGCAUGCAGCCCCUGUCAUGUACCGCCUGUUUGCUCAAAUCAAUCAUGACCCUUUCAUGUGAAAUCUUUAGUGUUGUGAGCCCUUAAAAGGGACAGAAAUUGUGCAUUCAAGGAGCUUGGAUUUUAAGGCAGCAGCUUGCUGAUGCCACCAGCUGAAAAAAGCCCUUCCUUCUCCAACUCGGUGUCUGAGAAGUUUUGUCUGCAGCUCAUCCUGCUACAGAAUGAACUCCUUGUAAUUCUACAAGAUAUGCCAUGGGCCUUUUCACAGGGGACACAGGCUUCUUAAAACAACCCGGCUUCCUCACCCUAUGUCCUUUAUUUACAAAGCUGUGCUCCUAUUCAUGAGCAUGGAAUGUUUUUCCAUUUGUUUGUGACAUCUCUUAUUUCUUUCAGGGGUAUCUUGUAAUUCUCAUUAUAUAUAUCUUUUGCUUCCUUGGUUAGCUGUAUUUUUAGGUAUUUUAGUCUUCUUGUGGCAAUUGUGAAUGGGAUUGCAUUCCUGAUUUGGCUCUUGGCUUAAUGUUAUUAACGCCACAUUUUUUAAAUAGACAAAAAUAUGAGAUUAAAAAUGUUGAAUUUUACUAACAAUAAAAGUUGUUCAAAGGAAAACUAUAAGGUUCUUGUUUCAACUCUGUCAUAGGAAGAACAGGACAGUGAGCUGGCACAGAGUUAGGGAAACUGACUGUGUCUCAUAUUGGCUAGUGAGAGUGAUCUGUUGGAAUUGUAUAUCAAAAUUUUAAUGUACAUACAUUUUGUCUAGCAAUUCUACUAUUGGGUAUUUAUAUAGUACAUAUAAAUAUAAAUGUAUAUGUUUAGUAAAUAUAUACUUAUAGUUAGUAAAUAUAUUUUAUAUCUAUUUAGUAAAUAUACUAAAUGUCAGGCCUCUGAGCCCAAGCUAAGCCAUCAUAUCCCCUGUGACCUGCAUGUACAUACGUCCAGAUGGCCUGAAGCAAGUGAAGAAUCACAAAAGAAGUGAAAAUGGCCUGUUCCUGCCUUAACUGAUGACAUUACCUUGUGAAAUUCCUUCUCCUGGCUCAUCCUGGCUCAAAAGCUCCCCCACUAAGCAACUUGUGACACCCACCUCUGCCCGCCAGAGAACAACCCCCUUUGACUGUAAUUUUCCUUUACCAACCCAAAUCCUGUAAAAUGGUCCCAACCCUAUCUCCCUUCACUGACUGUCUUUUCGGACUCAGCCAGCCUGCACCCAGGUGAUUAAAAAGCUUUAUUGCUCACACAAA